AGACGCGCGCUGCAGGAGCGCGGAACAUGGCGCGGCACGGGCCACCGUGGAGUCGGUUGGACGCGCAGCAGGAGCGCGACGUGCGGGAGCUCGUCCGGGGUGUCGCCGGCCUCCAGGACGAGGCAGACCCCAACUUCCAGCUCGCCCUAAACUUCGCCUGGUCCAACUUCAGAUUUCAUCGUUUCUUGGAUGUCAACAGCCACAAAAUAGAAAAAACAAUCGAAGGAAUUUAUGAAAAAUUUGUCAUUCAUUCUGAUCUAAGCAAAGCUGCUAGUUGGAAGAGAUUAACGGAGGAAUUUCUAAAUGCACCACUUCCCAGUAUAAAGGAAAUAAAGGUUGCCUUCAAUUAUGAGAUCUCCCUGUGUAUUUUACUGUUUCUAUCUGAUUAUCCAAUUUGUUUCAGUUAUGUUUAAACA